AUGUCCUCUCGGGCAGAGAGGCUGGAGGAGACAGGCAACCUGCUAGCCGGAGUGGAAGCGCGCCCGCCUCCCGCCGGGCCCUCCCUCUCAGGGUCCCCACGCUGCGACCCUCCCAAGGGCAAGUCCGGGGCCACCAGGUCUUUGGUCUCCGUCCAGCUCCUCAGGGGCCGCCCCAUAGGGACUGGCGGGGGCACCGUGGGCGAGAGGCCCUGUCCCCAACACGUGAACCCCUGCGGCCGUCCUCCCGCCUGCUCUAACGCAGCCCAGGGGUACCGCGUCUCCCUCCGCCUGCCGCCGGCUUACCUGGCGGGUGGGCAGGGCAGGGUGGCGGGAAGCGGCGGCCGGGCAGGCGCUGGACGUGGGCUAGGCGCCAGGUGCAGGUGGCGGCGGCUGCGACUCCGGUUGCUGUCGCCACAGUUGCGGCUCAGUAGAGCUCCUCCUCCGCCGCCGCCUCCUGCCUUCCCGCUGGGCCUCCCGCGUUGCCUGGAGAGGCAGAACCGAGGCUCGGCUUCCACUUGGAGUCUCCCAGGUGAGCUCCAGCCUGCGACGUCGGCAGGGGCGAGGCCCCACUUCCGCGCCUGCGCGCCAGCCUCCCGCCCCGCCCCAGCCCUACCUGAGCGCUCCAGGGGCGCCUCACGUCCAAAGGAGGAGUCUUCUUCCAAAGAAGAGCCUUUGGUAUUUGGCAGAGCCUCGCCAAUUUGGGGCGCACCUCCCCUUCCUGGGAUGCUCUCAGAAGGCAAACCAAUUCCCAGAAGAGAGGGAAAAACAGCCACAACAGAGAGAACCUUUGCUGUCCCUGUUUGGAAAGAGAUUGGGAUUUCCUGGAGAGGGCUUGCUUCUACUGCAGGUUUGUUUAAAAGCUCAACAUCUAUUCUGGAAGAGAACAACGCAGACUCCAGGAAGAUGGAGAAAAGGCAUUUGCUGCCCAAGGUAGAAUCCCAUCACCAUACUCCUUUCCUACAUCCAAUCACAAAAUCAGAAUAUGCCAAUUCUCUAUUCCCAAGCGUGUCAUUUUGGAAUGUGUCUUGCUGCUCUUCUCAUCAAAGAUCACCACACCAUGAAGAAGUCUGGGGCGAAAGGCCAUGUGGAGUGAGAGGCUCAGCUUCCCAGAUGAUCUCACUGAGCACAGCCCCCAGCCACCUGCCAGCUCAAUGCAACCUGGUGAUGGACCCAAGCAAAUACCAGCAGAAGAAUCACCUGGUCAACCCACAGAAUCAUGAGAAAUACUAAUUUGUUGUUGUCUUAAGCCAGUAAGUUUUGAGAGAGUGUUUUAACUGUUUCACCUAAGUUUGGUCUCUUAACAUGAACAUAAGCACUUUUUUGCAUUUGUACAUCCUUUGUACUCUUCCUGUUCAUACCGAGAAAGCUUUUGCAAUGCAAAAGCUCAAAUGUAUUGGAAUUUUAGAAGUUUAAGCCUUGAAGGACUCUGUACAAAACCAUGCCAAAAACCAUAUAUUUUGAAGAAUAUGUUCUCAGUCUGAGCCAGUUUUCUAUUUCCACCUCAAAUCUUGAUUGGUGCAGACUGGAGAAAGGAGAAGAGAGUCAGGGGUAAGACCGUGGGUCGGAGGUGGAUAUCGACAAUGUACCUGAGUAAAAGCCCUGUAGCCUCUCACCAUGUUGGAAUACCAUAUGGCACAACUACAUGGACCGCCAUUUACAUAGAGUAGGAUGUUUAGUACUGCGUCUUGACCUUUGAAACCAGACUGGUGAGAGGACUCACCAACAAAAGUGAAGCUAGGGUCAUAGGCCCUACCUUGGAGAUUGGUAAGACCCCAGAGUUAUUCCUUGCCCAAUGUUAAGUAAGAACAGAAAACAUUUCUAAAGAGGGUCCUGAGGCAGACAGGUCUUAAGCAGUCCCACAGCCCUCAUGUGCCCUAGAAAGAUGCAGAGCGCCCAGAAGCGGUUUUUCAGUGCAGGUGAGAAUGGUUUAGAUCCACAUGUUUUUGUAAAUUAGUUUUUAUUGGAAGAGAGGCAAACCCAUACAUUUACCUGUUGUCUAUGGCUGCUUUGACACUACAAUAGCAGAGUUGGGUAGUUGUGACAGAGAUCAUAUGGUACACAAAGCCUAAAACAUUUACUAUCUGGUCCUUUAUUUUUAAAAAGUCCUUAUAUUAGAUGAAACACAAAGAACUGGUAAAACUUAAGCCUUGUGUAAUAAUACAAAACAAAAAUAUACCAUGUAGACCAUAAUCAAAGGGCCCAUUGUCUUCAGCCGCUGACAUUGGGACCAGGGUGUAGUGUCAGAACAUGAAAGCCUGGAUACCUACAAUGGCCUAAUUUUCUCAUACAAAUGCAUCCUACCACUCCCAUCCCAUACCUUAUGCUAGAUAGGAUCCAUGGAAUUAGCUGCAUCUCCAGUGAAACAGGAAAAGUCCCUGAUUUUACUGAGAUUUAGCUAUUGUCACAUGGUGUAACAGGGAUUUAAGAGAAAAAAUAACCUCAGGUAUAGACAUAGGAAAAUAAUGUUAGAUUAAGUUUCUUAUACACCUGGUUCUGUCUUCAGAAACUGGCACCCACUAUAAAGCCUUCCAUAGUGAUAAUUAUCGCACAAAAUCGAUACAAAGGAAAUACCUGCUGAAUGUUCUGCCUCAGUAGGUUUUCCUUUGGUCUUUUACCUUAGAAAACUGCAUGAUAGCAUUUUUCUAUUAUUUUGACAUUUCAUGUAGGAAGCAUGUUAUUCACAACUUAUGUUUUAUAAAAUCUUUUUCUGAUGAUGAUGAUGAUGACACUUGUUAAUUUCCAUCUCCUUCCUUCACUGUAAGUUUUUCUAUUCCCUGAGACAACUAUUUCUCUCACUUGUCCUAAACCCCAAGGAUACAAGAGAUGCAUAGGAAAAUAUCUAUGAAGUGUGUGGGAGGAGACAACAGGGCAGGGUUCCAGAGGUCUGUGGUUUAUUGCACGUAAAACACUGGAAAGUGCUUUGGAUGAUAAGGAAGUAGCUUGUUGUCCUUUGCAAUGGCCUGACAUUCUUACACUGAGAAAAUCUUACUCCCCACUUUGAGCUGGGAUGUGGGAGCUGGGAGGACAUUUACUGAGUAUUAACUCUGUGCCAGGAAUUAUUCCUACAUUAUCUCAUUUAGUCUCCGGAAAACCCUACGUAACAGGUGAGAAGACCUCAGUGACAAGCUCAAAGAUGCAUAGCUAAAGAGCUGAAAUGUAAAAGCAGGUCUGCCAGACUCAAAAACCCAUGCUCUAUAAACUACAUCAUAGAAGUUGUAAAAUAAUUUUACCUUGAAUCCAAGGGUGAAUAAUUUGUCAUGGUUAGCUUGCCCUUUGGCAUUCAUAAACAAUUUCUACUGUCCCAGUUUUUGUUCCAUUCAUAUAGGAGUAACAUGUGGAAGUAUUAAGCAAUAGAAGGCUUUGUUUUCAUGUAUAAAUUUUUACGAUAUUUUCAAAUAUAAUAAAGCCAAAAUUGUUAAUUUCA